GCUUCUGCCAGCCCUACGCACCGGGUGAGGGUGGCAGACGAGAAAGGAAGGAUGGGGGCUCUGGAUUCCUGGGUCUGGAGCUCCAUCUGCGUCCACAUCUGUCCACUCCAUCAAGGGGAUGCACUAACAUAUUAGCCCCCAGAAAAACCACUUGGGGAACUUGCUAAAUUUUCAGGUCCCGCCUUCCAAGAGAGGCGGAUUCCACGGUGCUGGGGGAGGGGUUCGGGAAUCUGCGUUUUAAACAAGUGCCCCAAGUGAUCCUGAUGCAGGCGGUUCACUGACCUCACUUUAAGAAACUCUGCUCUGGAUGAAGAAUUAAUUUUGGGAGGUGGCUUGGAGGAAGAGAGAGCUCAGGAAGUCUGCACUGAAGAAUUAUGAAAAUCUUAUUUUGGCAUCAUUCAUUCAUUCACCAACUGAGGCUUAGCUGGGCCUGGGCCUGAGGUCUCUGCCACUCUGUCUACUGUUUCUAUUACUGAUGGCUGAAAAAAAAAAUGCUCCCAGCAGCCUCCCCAGGAGCCCCGUGGCCAUGACACAGCUGCUUCUGUUCCUUGUGGCUCUCCUGGUUCUGGGUCAUGUGCCAUCAGGGAGAAGUGAAUUCAAACGGUGCUGGAAGGGUCAAGGGGCCUGCCAAACUUACUGCACAAGGCAAGAAACUUACAUGCACCUGUGCCCGGAUGCGUCCCUGUGCUGUCUCUCCUAUGCAUUGAAACCUCCACCGGUCCCCAAGCAUGAAUAUGAGUAGCUGGUUCCUGCUGUCCAAUAAAACACAGGUUGCCA